GUCACAUGCAACAUUUACAGGAAACUGGCUAGAAGACAGCAGGGGAACUCGAGAAGUUGGUUGUUUUCAGCAGAUUAAAACAAUACAGGUUAGUGCUUUUUGCCCCCUGGAAAACUUUUCGUAGCCACUCUAAAAUACCUAAUUCUCUUUCCUUGAACUGUCUUUAACGAUUUCUUUAAUGUGAAGAACUUGCUUUUUGGCUUUGAAUGUAAGAGCCAGCGCACAGCUGUUAACUGCACGUUGUUAGAGGAACAAACGCUGAGCCAUUAUGGUGAAAAUGAAAUUCUCAGAAUCUCUUGCUUCCCUGUUUAGAACUUCUCUGCUUCUGAAAGAACAAAACUUCGGAUGUUCUUUAAAUAACUUAUUUCGUGGAAUUCAGCUAGGCCUCUUGUCAUUUUUACCUGUUAAUGUAAAUGUGAAACGGGACAGAUCAGCCUGUGUUUGCAGACAUCUGUGGGGCAUUCAAAGGGUGUUAGAAAAUACAGAAAUACUGUGCAUAAAAACGUGCUUGCGAGGUUAUAUGCAAAAGUUUGUUGUUUUGUGGGGUUUUCAUCUCAUAAAACUCAUCUUUUGGCUUGUAUUUCAUGUUAAAAUAGUAUGUCAUUAUAAAUUCUUAAGUUUCCUUUUUUUAUUUUUUCUACUGUCCUCCUUCCCCCUUUUCUUUCCUUCCUUCUUUUACUAACACAAAACAGGAGUAGAGAAGCAGCAGUAGGGACAGCUUGAAUAUGAGACGAGGAAAUCCUUUUCCCGGCACCAGAGUUUAAGGAGCAGGCACAGCCCAGAGCAAAGCCCAGCAGGCCGUGAAGAGGCCGUGAGGUGUGACGGUUGCCAGAGCUUUAUGUCUUCAGCCUUGUGCUUCCUAGAGAAGAGUCUGCAAAAGAGCCAGAAAGACGGCUAGAGGGUUGGGAAGCAGCCGUCCAGAAACAUAGAAAGGGCCCAAGAUUAUUCUUCCUGAGGCCAAUGAGGGACAGUUUAAUUACGCAGUGGCCUGCUGCUUUCAGACCUGUAUGUGGAAAAAGAAAACGUCUCAAAUCCAAGUUAAGAGAAGGAAGUUCCUACAUUAUUGGACUGCUGUGCAGCUCUAGGACAGGUUAGCCAGAGAGGCUGCUGAACUCUUUCUGGGUGUUUUUGGGAAACAUACUAGACGGCAUCUUUGACUGUGUUAUUGUGUUAACUGAGACAGGGAGGAUAAGGAGGAGAGGAGAGCAAGAUCAGGAACUUCCUGUUUCAUGUCUUCAUUCUAGCCCAAAGUGUUGUAAAAUGUGUCUGUAUGAUAAACAACGAAGGGGUGAGGGGCUCGUGGACUCAACUUGUUUAUAUCCUAGUAAUGCCAAAUAACUAGAACAGUGAUGAAAGAGAAAAAUCAUGGUUGAUUCUGUCCUCCAAUUGCCACAUUUUUUUCAUAUUUUACCACCAAGUUGUACAAGAAAAUGGAGACAAAGCUGACAGAGAAUAAGAGAAGAUUCUAAGCUGGACAUAUCAGCCCUAGUGGUUUCAGAAACCCCGUGCUAGCUCUGACAGAGCCAGCCCACAUUGUUAUCAGGUUUGGAGGGAUGGAGGGAAGAUUGGAUUUAUCACUGGUUGGAGCCCUUUGCACAAAUGCCUGUAGGAGACACGCACUUGGGAACUGCAGUAGGAAGGCCUCUUGUACCUGGUACUGCCCUUGAGCCCCAGGAAGAGGCUUACAACUUAGCAGUGGCUGGACAUCCCUCGAAGGAGCUCUUCUUUCAGUUUUGUUUUGCUUUGUUAGUUGGCUAUACAGCCUUGCUGUUUCAGAAGUUUUAUAUUCUGCAAAUCUGCUGCUCACAGUAGAAAGGGACUUUUUAUCUUUUUAUUUUGUUAGAAUACUUUCCAGAUGGGCCUGAUGUCUUUUUUUUUUUUUUUUUUUUUUUUUUUGAGAUGGAGUUUUGCUCUUGUCGCCUAGGUUGAAGUGCAGUGGCACCGUCUCGGCUCACUGCAACCCCUGCCUUCUGAGUUCAAGCAAUUCUCCUGCCUCAGCCUCCCAAGCAGCUGGGAUUACAGGCAUGCAUCACCACACGUGGCUAAUAUUGUAUUUUUAGUAGAUACGGGGUUUCACCGUGUUGGUCAGGCUGGUCUUGAACUCCUGACCUCAGGUGAUCCGCCCGCCUCAGCCUCCCAAAGUGCUGGGAUUACAGGUGUGAGCCACUGCACCCAGCUGCCUGAUGUCAUUUUUGUAAAUGCAUCCUUCCAAAAGCUGUUUGUAUUUCUUCUGGGGGUCCUUAUUCUCUCCUAUUUCUCAGCCCCUUCCCCAUCUUUCCACUUUCACUGCGCUGUGUUCCAUUGUGUUUGAGAUGCAAAAAAUGGCUUAUAAAGUGUCAUCAUUAUACAAAACCUCUGAUCCCCAGGUUCUGAAAGAACGAGUGGAGACACAGAAUGGCAGAAGGUAACAGAUCCUGUUGGGUGGUAGAGAGCACCUGGAGUAUUAAUCUUGUGUGUAAUUUUUAGAUAGGAAUGACUGCCAAGUUGAAUACUGAGUUAAGUUUAAAGGUCAAAGUGGAAAGAGAUGAAGUCACCUUUAAUCUGGAGAAAAAAUGGUAAAUUUUGUGGGGAGGAACAGUAUGGACACAUUCCUGAACUCUCUAAAUAGAAGAGGAAUGAGGCUAACUUCACAAAUCUCUCUUCUUCCUCAACAUAGGCAGGCCUCUCCUCCCUGAAUCCCAGAUAAUACCAGAGUGGCACUGCGGGUCGACAUCCACAGAUGUCUGAGUGACCCUGGUUUCAGAGGGAUAAAAUGGUGAUAUAUACCAAACAUUCAUGCUAGUGGGGAAAAGAAAGUUAAACUCUGAUAAGUGCAACUUUUACAACUGAACUCAUCCUUGGUAUCGUUUUGAGUUGGCAUGAACAAAUCUGGAGGCCCAGGUCUCUGGAUUUCUCAGAAAGAAGUUCCCGGACAUUUGUAAGGUAUUAUUGUUAUCACCAUCAUAUUGGGAAAUACUAAGAACUAUAGGUUUUGGGGGAGUUUUAAUUGUGAUAAAGGACACAUAACAAAAUUUACCAUCUUAACCAUUAAGAUACAGUUCAGUAGCGUUAAGUAUAUUCAUAUUGUGCAACCAAUCUCCAGAACUCUUUAUUUUGCAAAACUGAAACUUAAACCCAUUAAACAACAACUCCCCAUUCCCUUUCCCCCAGCUCUUGGCAGCCACCAUUCUACUUUCUGUCUUUAUGAAUUUGACUUUUCUAGGUACCUCAUAUAAGUAGAAUUAUAUAAUAUUUGUCGUUCUGUUUCUGCUUUAUUUCACUUAGCGUAAUGUCCUUAAGGUCCGUCCAUGUUGUUAGCACGUGUCAAACAUUCCUUCCUUUUUAAGGCCAAACAUAUUUGUAUGUAUAUAUCACAUUUUCUUUAUCCCUUCAUUCAUCAGUGGACAUUUGGGCUGCUUCUACUUUUUCGCUGUUGUGACUAAUGCUGCUAUGAACGUGGGUUUGCACAUAUCUUUGAGAUCCUGGAUUCAGUUCCUUUGGUAUGUCCCCAGAAGUGGAAUUGCUGAAUCAUAGGUAAUUCUAUGUUUGGCUUCUGAGAAUUAUCCAGCAAUUGUGUCUUCUUAUACCACUCUUCCUCCCAAAACACAAACUUGAAGAUACCUCAUAUUAUAAGAUCAUUAUCAUUUUUCUUCAGGAAUGCCUCAAACAAAAUGUUCAUGUCUUGCUUCUGAGCAGUAAGGAUGCAGAGGGGACUUGGGCUGUUGUCCCAGGAAAAGGAGCAAGACCAAUGGGGCUAUUCUGGAGGGGUGACCAUGGUAGGUGUUUGGAUUACAGAUUCUGUGCAAGGAAGUGGUAGGAAAGAUGUGAUAGACGGCCUGACACAGUGCUGUGUGGUGAUUCUUUUGCUGGAGAUGUUGUCUCCUAACUAAAAUAUCAUGAAUACUAAUGUAUACUCUGUAACUCUACCAGGGAAGGGAUUGCCUAUGUGCCUGAUUGAUUUUUUACUCUGCCAUUUCAAUUUCCCUCUAUUUCGUCAUCAGUCAGAAGGUUGGUGCUGUUUAAAGGGGAAAAAAAAGCUCUAAGUGUCCCCUUCUCCCAAAAAAAGGAACCAGAAAAUGACAAGAAGAGUUGCAUUUGUCUAUGAAAGUGCAUAGAAAGCUUUUCCUGGAAAAGAAUAAACUGGGAAAAGAUGAGUCCUUGAAGUAGAACCCUGUCAUAGUGCAACAAACUGAAUUUAAGAGGCAUCUGUUCCCAGCUUAUACAACAUCCAGUACCAGUUCCACAGUAGGUAUUCACAUUACCACUCAGAUUGUUAUUUCUCAAUGCUAAUGAGAAGCUACUGCUUUGAGACUGUCUAACUAGCUAGACACUUACCAGACUUUGUUUUGAUAUUUUCUGGUAUGAAUUAGGCUUCCUUUCUAGUUGCGUUCAUGCCCAGAUUUUAAUAUGACAUAUUUUAAGUUAACUCAUUGUAUUGUUUUGUAACCUAGAGUGGCUUAAAAACAGAGUCAUUUGUUAUAGUAGGAUAUGUGUUCGCACACACAAAUAUACGUGUGUGUAUGUGUGUGUGUAUAAUGGGAGGAAUUCUCUAGAGCAUAUGUUUCCUAAAUUAGAAGUCACUAAGUGAUAUCUUGGAGCCUACAAUUAUUUGGAAUACUGCUAUCUUCAGACUAGGAAGUUAUGCAUGUAUUAUACAUAGAGAUUCAUUUGGGGGGUUUGCUAGUAAACUGUAAUUCUUUCAGUAAGUCACUGCUUUACUGAAUGGUGAAGAUUUGGAAUGUCUUCUUUGAUUUCCAGGCCAACAAUGGAUAGAUUUGGUCGUCCUUGAAGCAUUUAGAGACCUGUAGAAUGAACUUAACUUCUGAAAACUGGGUGCGGGGCCAAUAGAGGGGCUGCUCAAUACCUCACCAGCCUGCUACGCGGAAGGCUAGAUGGAGGGCUGCUAAAGGAAGAGAACUGCUGUUCCACCUCCGCCUCCUCCCUGCAGUGUGGCUUCUUAGGCAAGUCCCAGUUUAGAAGUCAUCUAACUAAGUGAACAUUCUUGAACUGCCACCAGACCUCUCCUAAAACUUUUUUCUAAGCAAACAAUAUAUGCUUUCAGACUUUCUCUUCUUCCCUCUUCUUUUCCCCUUCUCUCCACUCCCUACUUUCGCCUCUGCCAUUUCAUGCCCAUCACCUUGUGAAAGCUCAGGGCAGAAUUUACCUACAUGGACAGCAUGCUUCCUUCCCUGGCCCUGUCUCUGAGCUUUUUAUUCCUCUUCCCCAGAGCAUUUAAUAGCCUUCCCUGCAAAACAGAGGAAAGUCAAGGCUGAUGAGCAUAGUUAUCAGAAUAAAACUGUUUAAGAGGUUUUAUGUAAGAAAAAUAAUUUGGAAAAUAACAAUGUUUUUUAUAAGAUCCUGAUGAAUCAGGAAGGAUAAAUAGUUUACUUUUUUUUGAUAGAGAGAGACUCACUAUGUUGCCGAACUCCAUCUGGAGUGCAGUUGCUAUUCACAGGUACAGUCAUGGCACACUGCAGUCUCGAACCCCUAGGCUCAAGCAAUUCUCCUGCCUCAGCCUCUCUAUGUUUUAAAGACUUCCUUUAAGGGUCCAUAAGGAGGUAGCUGUAAGGGAAGGGGAACUAAAAAGGCCAGAGGAUAAUUUUCUCUAAAAGGCAAAAAUGUUAGGUUAUUCAAAAACUAUUUUUUUCCUCUACUUCAGUGCCAGGAACAUCUGGCCUCAGGAAAAGUUUAGGAAAGAUGCUGUUGUCAUCAUUUAAAUCUUAAAGAGGUAGGAAAAAAAUAAUCUUGGAUUUUUUACAACUAGAAGGGACCUUAGAGAGUUAUAUCCUUUUAUUUUUAGAUUUGGAAACUAAGGCCCAGAGAGAUUAGGUGAUUUGUCUAUGGUCAAAGUAGCUCAUUAAUGAUGGUAGAGGGUGCAGAACAAGGCCCCUGGCUACACACUGGUGACAUAAGGGGGAAAUGUUGAAGGGCCCCAAGGACUUGGGAAUCUGAAAGUAGGUGCACCUCUGGGAUCUACAGAGGCCAGAUCUGUGCCUAAUGGGAGUAGAGUAACAGAUUGAAGAUUUGAGGAACUUCCAGAACUCCAGCAAAGUGAGCUCUACGUAAUUCCUGGAAGACAGCACAGCCAUAUGGUUGGAAUUUUGUGGGUAGAAAGCUAAUCCAUCCUACCUGGAGAAAGGUUGUGGGCAAUGAACUGGUCCUCAUGGAGCAGAGAGGAAAAAUUUCCAAUGGUUGCCCAGUAUUGGCCUGGAAAAUAGGUCCUGAAUCUUGUGGACAUGAGUGUGGAUUGGUAAGUAUGGAUGAAGAUCUUUUGUGAAGUGUCUGUUGUGAUGCAUUAUCAGGGCUCACCACGGCAUGGAUUAAGCAGUCCUCAGAAGGGUUAGCCAUCCUUAGCACUGAUUCCAACACCCCUGAACCACAUUCUGAAUGCUAAGUCAACUUCCUGGGUACCAUUAGCUCAGAAAGGUAUAUUCUGGACAAUGGACAUGGUCACUGGAAAGAAAUGGCAUUUUUUUGUAGAUUCCGGGGUGCCCAGCAGCCUCUUGUGAAUUUUUACUCAGACAUUCUGAGUCUGAUCCCUCUGGCUCCCAGAUAAAAGGGAGAUGUGGGGACCUCUAUGAUAACGCUCUGUGCUUGAUGUAGUGUUCUACCCCUCCCCAAGAAUGCCACUCUUAGGGGUCUUUUCAGGGUAAACAGCAGCCUCUCCUAAGUGUCAGGCUUACUUUGUUGUUGCUCCUCUUCAAAAUGCCACAAACAUUAUUAAAAUUAAAAAAUGAGAUGUAAUACAUGGGUCCUGCUAUUAGAAAUCACAAGGCCUGGCCAGGUGUGAUGUCUCAUGCAUGUAAUCCCAGGACUCUAGGAGGCCGAGAUGGCCUUGAGGAUUGCUUGAGCCAGGAGUUCGAGACCAGCCUGGGCAACGUAGGAAGACCCCAUCUCUACAAAAAAUUAAAAAUUAGCCAGGUUUGGUGGCAUUCACCUGUGGUUCCAGCUAAUCAGGAGGCUGAGGCAGGGGGAUCACUUGAGCCCAGCAGGUCAAGGUCAAGGCUGCAGUGAGCCAUGAUCACACCACUGCACUCCAGCCUGGGUAACAGAGGAAGACUGUCUCAAAAAAAAAAAAGAAAGAGAAAGAAAGAGAGAAGGAGGGAGGGAAGGAAGGAAGGAAGGGAGGAAGGAAGGGAGGGAAAAAGAGAGAAAGAAAGAGAAAGGAAGAAAGAAAGGAAAGAAAGAGAAAGGAAAGAAAGAAGGAAAGAAGAAAAGAAAAAGAAAAGAAAAUCAUAAGACCUUUUUUUGGACACUGGAUGUUUUCAAAGUUUUUUCUCUUUGUUUUUCUUGUUUGGCAUUUUCCCUUAAUUCAGAUUUAUUUAUUAAGUAUCUUCCAUGUGGAUCUUAUAUUCAAGUUAAAAGAUGUGGACAAAAAACAAUAAAUCUAAAAAAUACUAGGUGAUGUAUAUUAGGAAUUUAGAAGGGAUACAUGCUGUGGAGAAAGAAGUCUAGCGGGGCUAGGAGGAGCAGAGCACAGUGGUGGAGGAUGGGUGUAGGUGAGCUGGUAAGGGCAGCUGUCAUGGAGAAAAUGGUGAGAUAAUUCACCAUGUAGCCACAUGGGGAAAGCCUGAGGACGCAGAAGCGGAACAUGCCUGGAGUAUUCAAGGAGUAACAUGGAGCCAGUAAUUUGGAGAAAAGGAGAUACCGCUGGCCCUCCAUAUUCACAAGCUCUGCAUCUGUGGGUUCAGCCAACUAUGGAUCGAAAUAUGCAACUUCAAAUUAUCUUCAUUCAGGAAGGAGAACCCUGAGUUCUUCUGGGUUGGAUCUAAGCAUGGAAGCCAGCUACCGUGUUAAGAGCUGCCUUAUAGAGAGAUGCAUGUGCAGAGAACUGAGGGAGACCUGUAACCAACAGCCAGUCAGGAAAUGAAUCCUGCCAACAACAUCUCCUUAAGGACCACACUGUGGAAGGAAGACUGGAAAGGCCUCAGCAGGGGAGAAACCAUGUGAUGGAGGCUCAGAGUGGACUUCUGAUCUAGUAGUGGCUUCAGGAAGGGACGCCAGACUUGCCAUUCCAGCAGGGGUCGAGGCCUCCCUGUCUCGUGAAGAGGAAGGUGUGAAAUCCUCUUAUAGACACAUGAUUCUCUUUCAGUGUAUUUUCUUUAUUCCAUCUUGACCUCAGGAUGGAUAACUCAUCAUCCCUUUUGGCACGGAUCAAAAUCCCUGGAUAAAUGCCAACCUUAAGUUUGCCUGCAUGUGUGUAACCAUGGCCAAGGUAAACUGGUCUCUUGGGUUUCUUUUGAGUUGAAAUGAGCUGAGCUGUUUGUUUCCUCUGAGCCAUAUACAGAUGCUUUUUGAACUAUCUUUGUGUUUGAGGGAAUUUUUUUUCAUGGUAUCAGCACACCACUUCCUCCAAGUCAUUACUUUGAAACAGUUUUGUAGAGGGAGAUAUUCCUGCUGGCCACCAGCCUAGCCAAGCAAAGUGAUGACUGAGGGAUGGCAGUAAAGCUUUAUUAGUGCACUUCAUGUUUUUGGAUGAGUUCAUGAAAUGAUUUCUCAUCCACUAAUUUUGGCAAAUAGAGGGUGGGCUGUCAUCUGAGCUCAGCAGUAGAAAACAGCACUUUGUUAAUACCAAGCAUUGGCUCCCCUGUUUGAAUGAUACUCAGAAUUUCAGCUAAAAUAAUGUCCUCCGAUGACCUUUGCCUGCUCUUCUCUUUAUAAGAAUUCCACAGAACUCUUUUGAAUAUGGAUUUCCACUUAAUCUUUGAUACUUCCAGGCUCUUGGGUCCUGAUAAGUUUUAGAAACUGCAAGUUUAAGUGAAGCUGUUUUUAACUUCCCUUUUAUUUUGCUUUAAAUAUUUUUAGCAAUGAAUGACCUUUGAAUACUUUUAAAUGUUGCUAUACAAACAUAAACAGUGCUUUUACUAACAUAUUUUAUAAAUAUUUCCUUUUCCAUAAAUUCAUAAAUUGCUUUUGUCAUAAAAAUAGUAAUAUUUUAUAGUAUUUUAAGAGUAAAUUCUAAGCCUUUAAGAACUUUUAUGCCUACACUAAGGAAAAUAGGACUAGAGACUUAAAAUACAUAACCAUGCUACAUUUAUAGUGAUUGUUAUGUUCUCUGAUUCAUACAUUAAAAACUGAUGUGAUUCCAUAAAAUUCUGACUGUAUUUUUUUAAUGUAAUUGCUUAUUUUGUAUAGGAAGUGGGAGGAGUUAUCCUUGAGGCAAAUCACCACUGAAUUGACCCAUCCUUUUAUCAACUUUAUUUUUUUUUAAGCCCAAAUUCUAGCAAAGCAAUAACAGAAUAAAGCAGACUUGAAAAUAAGCAGUCUUCCAUUCCCUAGUUGGGUGAGACUAUCCGAAAAGCCUUUGAACAUUUUCUUAGUGAAAUGAAGAGGAGUCCUGUUCUCUGCAGUGGAGGAUUUGGAGACAAGUGGCUCGGCAUUCGGCUCUUGGAAUUUUAACUUAACUACUAAUUAGCAAUGGCUCUCUCCAGAUAACAAACCACUAAUGGAGUAAGAUAUACUAAUAAUGGAGAAGACAAUAAAUAAACCUAUCAAAUUGGCAAAGAUUUUGAAACGUCAUAAUAGCACAUGUUAAAAAGAAGAAAUGAGUACUGAUGGGAGUAUGCAAGCUAAAACUUUGAGAAAAUAAUUUAAUCGUAUGUAUCAAGAUUCCUUAAAAAAAAACUGUUCAUGUCUUCUAGUGAUUGUACUCUAAAAAUUUAUCCUAAGGAAAUACUAUAAAAUGAUUACAAAACAUUCAGAUGCAAGUAUAUUAAUUAUAAUAGGAUUUGUAAUAAUGAAAUUGGAUGCAAUUUAAAUGUCUAACAAUAAAAAAUAUUUACAUAGAUAAUAGAACAUCCAGAAAAUGAGAUAUGCAACUAUUAAAAUUGUGUUAAGAGAAUAAUAUGGGGAAAUGUGAAAAAGAAGGAUAUAUACAGACGCACGUACACAUCCAAAGUAUGAUCCCAUUUUAAAUACAAACACAAAAAGAAAGAAAAACACUGGAAAGAAAUUCUAAGAUGAUAACUGGUUUUCUCUGGGUAUUAAUGGGUGAUUUUUAAAAAUAGGUGGGGUAUGGUGGCACACACCUAUAAUCCCAGUACUUUGGGAGGCCAAGGCAGGAUGAUUGCUUGAGGCCAAGAGUUUGAAGGUAGCCUAGGCAACAUAGCAAGACUACGUCUCUACAAAAAUAAAAAAUUUGUAAAAAUUAGCCAAGCGAGGCAGCAUGCACCUGUAGUCCCAGCUACUCAGGAGGUGGGAGGAUUGCUUGAGCCUAGGAGUUUGAAGCUGCAGCGAGUUGAUCAUGCCACUGCACUCUGGCCUGGGUGAUAGAGCAGGAAUCUGUCUCAAAAAAAAAUAAAGUUAUUUAAGUGAAGGAAUCAAACUAUGAAAAGUGGGAGAAACUUAACAAAGUUAACCCUAGACAGUGUGUGACUGUACUAUGUGGUGUCUUCCUCCAACUAAAUGUCUUCUCUGAUCUCAAAAAAAUUCAACAUCAUAUGGGUUAACAUGGGUUAACACCUCUCUUCUCUUUUAAAUAAAAGACAACUUGAUUUCCUCCUGAUGCCUCAAUGAGAUCAUCUUAUCCCAGGAAAGGGAAUUACAAUUUAGGGUAAGAAAUAUUUGGGGGACAGGAGCCCCUUAGUGUCUUGCAUGAGACCAAGGGAAAGUUUGGAGGUGGCCUGAAGGUGGGGGCAGAGGCAGAAGCUGAGGCUGGGGAGCCCCAGAGAGGGACGACCCUCCCUCCUCCUCCUCCUGAUACCACCUUAAAGUCCUUUCCUUUGAGGACUCAGAACUGAAGUUUUAGUUUAGUGACAUUAUGAACUAAAUAUACUUUUGUGGGCUGGCCUAGCAAUAUAUCAUCAAGUUUUUUUGUUUGUUUGUUUUUGUUUUUGUUUUAUGGAAAUGGUCCUUGGAUUGAAACGACUAACCCCCAAAGGACUUUGGAGCCCUUUCCAUUUGCAUCCUAGUUUGCCUGGAUUAGUGCUGCUCUGACAGUGAUCUUGGUGAGGCUGCUCUUCAUAAUAUAAUAUGAGCUGGGCCUAAAUGAACACCUGCACAGCAUAAAACAGAGGGUAAAUUUCCUUCCACACAUCAUCAACGCAGAUAGGAGUGUAAGCUCCAUGACGGUGGACAAUUUUGUCUGUUUAAUCUUUGUAGUAUCCCCUAAAGCAACCUUGGAACAUGAAGAUACUGAGUAUUUGUUGAAUGGCUGCUGUGCAUGGAGCCCUAGCACAGCUGCUCGCUAGUUAACAGUGGCAUUAGAGACACACAAAGAUUAUAAAACACUUCUAUUUCUAGAAAGUCAUCUACAGUUUUGUGCGUUUUUCUUUUGGCUGGAGAAGAGGGCCGGGAGGUUGAGUGUGGGGCCAGAUCUGGGGGAAAAGGUCAGUGACUGCAGGGACCUAGAGGUUGGAGAAGCUCAUCUGGAAGGAGGAAGUGCUGGUGACAGAGAGGAGCCGUGGUCAGGAGCUGGGUGAGCUGUUGACCAAGGUGGAGGUUAUGUCGGGCUAUUCUGACACGUUGACCUUAGCCACAGUUCCCAGACCACUACUUAACUUGCCUUGCCAAGACACAACUGCCAUCCAAAGCCAGGAGUAGCACCCAGCUUGAGUUUUGUUUAAUCAUUGUUUCAUUUUAUUUUUGUGUGUUUUUUGUUUUUAUUUAAUGAUGGUGGGGGUGAGGCAGGGAGAGACCAUUUAUAUUUUUUUUCUACUUUGUCCAUUUAUCUUCCUGAGGGUGUCCUACAAAACAUAAACCACAUGUGGUUUUUAUACCCCAAAUUUUUGUGGUUUGUUAUUCCCAAACUAGUCAAUAUUUAAAUGUAGUCAUGGAGCUGCUUUUUACAUAAGCCACCAACUGAUCAUUUUGUUGGAAUGGAUCUGAAACAGAAUGAAAUGGUCCAAGUCUUUGGAUUAAGCAGCUUCCGUGUUGUGGGGAAAAGAGUCAACACGGAGCAGAAAGAAAAUAAAACCCACACAAAAUGGUGGGGAACUGGUCACUUUCUGAUCACACAUUUUCUGAUCCUACCACCACCCCUGCAUACGUAUUUGGAGUUAAAGGAACAACAUAUGUGCACAUGCUCCAGCAGGAAGCAUUUUCCUUUGUCUUUCCUGUGGCCUGAUAAGGUAUUGACCCCAUCGAGGCAACCCGAAAGUGUUUUUCCAACAAUCUGUUUCCCCAGUCAGUCAUUUGAAGAAUCCAGAGAAGCUGAAUGAGAGGAGGGAAGUUCUUGGAGGGAAUCUGGGGUCAUUCGAGUAGAACAAAUUCUGUUCUGGCCAAGCCACUGAGAAAAGCAGGAUCUGCUGAGAAACAGGAGAAAGAAUCACCCACGCCUCUGUGAUAUGUUUGGUAACAAAAUGUGAAGCUCCUUCACAGGAUCAGAGGUGAGUAGCUGUGGUGGUCUCCACUGCCCAGGCUGGAUGAGCAGAAUCGUCUGAUUGGCCUUUCAUGACUUUAAACGGAGCUCAGGCACAUGUAGACAUCCCAGGACCACCAGAAGCAGUGGCUCCCAGCCCCGACUGACCCCGUGCCCACUUGUAAUAACAGUAUUUUCUAAUGCCCUCUUCAAAAUCUUCAGUGAACCUUCACAAAUAAAAUAAUCUGACUUCACACACAAUUUCCCUCCAAAUCAAUGUAGUCUUAAUUUAAAAGAGAAAUGAAAGUAAUUUAUUAUAAAAUAACUUCAGUUUGUAAGUGAUCAGGUACAACUCAUCAGAAAACAAAAGUACAUGGUCAGGUGUUUGCGUGUAUGCGUAGGAUCACGGUGGGUGUGACAGCUGCCAUUGCAGGCUCUCUUGAGUUAAAGACUUCAGUAACACCAUUGACAUUGUCCUUGGGCUCAUGAUUUUCCAAAGGGGCAACUAACUCUUGGUAAAUAUCUGAACAAAACAAAGUAUUUCAUUUGUAUGACAUUUGCAUUACCGGAAAAUACAGGGAAUGAAUACAACAGUGCAAUAACUAUUUUGAGUUUAUGUAUAAAUUGGAGUUAAGGUCUAGGCUCAGAUAACUAGAAAUAGUUUUUUCAACCACAUCAAUAUGUAACAGGACCUUUGAAGGUCCUGUGGGACAAUUCUUUACUGAGUGAGACAGUGUGGUACAUUGCAGAUCAUCUGAAUCCCAGGAAGGCCCCCCAUUCUUAUGGCACUCACAAAUGCCCACCAUUUACUGUCCACCUGCAGAGUAGUUGGGUCUGCCUCUCCCAGGCAGCUGCACUAGCCAGGCCUGGCUUAUAUGCAGUCAGAGGGCCCCUAGGGGAGUCUUAGGUCACUGAGCCCUUCCCACAGUGUUCAGAUGGGUGGUGUCAGGCCCAGAGGUGCAGAGCUAUUUACCCUUGUUCCUGAGAAUCCAAGGGAGGGGCCUUUAGUGUCCAUAUAGUUCUGUCCUCCAGCAGGUGAUACUGAGUAGCCAUUUAGCUACAGAGAAGUCUGAAUAAGGAACAAUAUGGCUACUUUCACCAGCCCAGAAGUAAUUGUAAAGGCCCAUUCUGGCCUUUAUACCUAAUGAUUAGCAACCAUAGGGAACACACAGCUAUCUUCAUGCCAGCAGCUUCUCUCAGUGUGUGUGCACAAGUAUGUACCUGGCAGGAUGUGAAAAUGGGGCUUUCCACCAGUUUCUCCCUUGGGUUGCAAGAAGCCUCUUUCUAUCAUUCACAUGGGUUUUCCCCUGGGGGCCACUUAUAUUGGAUGCUGGUAACUGGGAAAUGUUUGCAUUUUAAUUAAAUUACCUAAGACAAGAUAGUGCUUAGAAAAAAAAAAGAAAAAAACAUGAAUGGUCUUUCCACAUGUGAAAUCAUUUUCUCUUCAAAGAAAUAAGGCAAGUGAUGUUCCAACCUCAGCACUUGUAUUUGUUUGCUUUUUGUUUCUUGGUUUUUGCUGAGCACAAAACUGCCAAACUCAGCAUGGAGAGGUGAACUUCCACGCUGUGUCCUCAGCAUCUAGGGUACUGGCAUCAGGCACACAGGGGCAUAGAAUGCAGAUUUGUUGGAUAUGAGUACGUGAAGCCGUUAUGGGACUGUCCUUUCUAGAUAGUCCUGGGCCUCUUUUUUUUCACCCUAGUUUGGUUCCCCUGCCUCUUUUCCAAGUCAGUCAUCUCACUAUUUUCUAACUCAUUCUCUUCCUGACACUGGCAAACAGCCCUGCGUGAGAAAGAGUCGUUAAAUCUGUUGGCAGGGCCCCCCAUUAUUGUCUUUUUAAAUGGCUGUCUUGUGUCAACCUGUUGGGAGAAGCAAGAGCCUCCCCAGGUCUUUUUGGAGAGCAAAUCUAACAAUUUCCACUUUAUCCUGGCACCUUUUUGCCUAGAGCCAAACGUGGAGCAGCAUAAUCACAACCCCAGGUUAAGUGAAAGUUAGAACUAAACUUAGAGCUGGAAGCUUGUAAAAUUCACUUACAAAUAUUUUCAAGCACCUGCAUUAUGCCAGAUACUGUUCUAAGUUGUUGGGGCAGCAGCAGUGACCAAGACAAACUCUGCCCUCGUGGAGCUGCCUCUCUGGUGGGAAGAGCAGAUCAGGCACAAAUACUGCAGAACAUGAGUGGAGUGAGGGGAGCAGCCAAGAGAACAGUGUCCUCAGAAGAGGGGACAGCAAGCACAAAAUCCCUAAGGCAAAGAGAUGGGGGGAGAAGGUAGGGAAAGAGGUCAAGGAAGGAGAGGGGAAGUGGGGGAGUGUCAAAUCCUCGAGGACCUUGCUAGUCAUGGCAAGGACUUUAGGUUUUACUUGGUAUAAAAUGGAAAGCCACUGAAGUGUUUGAGUCCGUGAAUGCUGUAGUUUGUAUGUGUCCCUUGAAGUUCAUUUGUCAGAAACUUAAUCCUGAAUGCAACCAUGUUCAGAGGUGGGACUUCUUUAUUUUAUUUUAUUUUUUUUGAGAUGGAGUCCUGCUCUGUUGCCCAGGUUGGAGUGCAGUGGUGCGAUCUCGGCUCACUGCAACCUCCGCCUCCUGGGUUCACUCCAUUCUCCUACCUCAGCCUCCCGAGUAGCUGGGAUUACAGGCGCCCGCCACCACGCCCAGCUAAUUUUUUGUAUUUUUAAUAGAGACGGGGUUUCACCGUGUUAGCCAGGAUGGUCUCGAUCUCCUGCCCUCGUGAUCCGCCUGCCUCAGCCUCCCAAAGGAGAGGUGGAACCUUUAAGAGAUGAUUAGGUCCUGAGUGCUCUGCCCUUAUAAAUGAAUUAAUGUCCUUAUCAUGGGACUAGGUUAGUUAUCACAAGAGUGGGUUCUUGAUAAAAGGAUGAAUUCUGUUUCCUUCCUUCCCUGCCUCUCAUUGUGCAUGCUCUCUUGCCUUCAGCCAUGGUAAUGACACGGCAAGAAGGCCCUCACCAGAUGUGGCCCCUCGACCUUGGACUUCUCAGCAUCCAGAACCGUAUCUGGCCUUUUCAUAAAUUACUCAGUCGCCAGUAUUCUGUUACAGCAGCACAAAACAGACUAAGGCAAUGUAUUUUUUCUGAGCCCUUAAUUUAAAACUUCUUUACUGCAGUAUCUCUUCACAUGUGGUACUAGAAGUGUUAGCACUAAGACCUCGGGGAAGAGAAGCCAAUUUAGCUCUUCUACUGGCCACAAAUCCAACAAUACCUAGUCAAUUCCUUGUUUUAAGAGAUGGCUUCAAGCAGAAUAAACUCUUCCUAAGAAUUUAUAACUAUAAAGCGCAGAGUUGGCUCUAGGUGGACCAAGACUUUUCCGGGACUGACAUUGAUUGAACAUCUGUUAAGUGUCAUUCAGGCAUCCUGCCAGCAUAAAAGAUGAGUAAGAUGGGGCCUGCGUGUCAGGCCCUCACUGUCUAGAGUUGUGUUGCCCAGUGUGGUAGUGGCUCUGGAGCACUUGAAGUGCUGCCAGUAGUAAAGUAAACACCAGUUUCUGAAGACUUCUUGUGAAAAAAAGAGUAUAAAAUACCUAAUUCAUAGUUCUUUUCAAAUGUUUAGUACAUGUUAUAAUGAUACUAUUUGGGGGGAUUUUCAUUGGUUUUUUUGAUACUAUUUUUGAAGUAGUGUGUUAAAAGAAAAUAUUACAAUCUCACCUAUUUACUUUUACUAUUUCUAACAUAGCUCGUAGAAAAUAUAGAAUUGCACACGUAACUCAAAUUAUAUUUCUACUGAACAGUGCUGAUCUAGAAAAAAGGGUCUGUUCUUUUGUUGGUUGGACUUUUAUUUUUACUUUUUUAUUGCCACUAAUAAUGGGUGUUCAGAUUUUGAGAGUUUACUCCUUUUCUGGGAAGAACCACUUGUUCUUUGACCAUUGUAGGGGAGCCCUCAUUCUAUCCAGUUUCUCCAAGAGCAAAAGAAAUUAUUUUGAGAAGUAAAAGGUAACUUCUGUAACUCUGUAAGUUACCUCUACAAGUCUGAGCAUUUUUACACUAGAUUAAGCAAACCUCUUUAACAGCCUCUAGUGGAUAAGGAAGGGAAUGAGCCACAAGUCUUUUUUUUUUAAUGCUUUUUGUUAUGGAAACAUUUUAAAUAUAUAUGAAAAGUAGACAGAACUGUGUAACAAACUGCUGUGUACUCCUCACCCAGCUUCAAGAAUGGCUAUUUCAUGAUCAAUUUUGUUUCAUUUGUACCCCUACCCACUUUCCCUCCUUUUCUAUAUUACUUUGGAAACAAGCCCAGGCAUCAUAUUUCAUCCACAAAUAUUUCAGUAUAUAUCUCUAAAAGUUAGGGAUUCUUUGUAAAAUACAAUAUAACCACAGUAACAUUAUCACACCUAACAAUUAUCAAUAUCUUAAUAUCAUUAAAUAUCUGAACAAUAUCCAAAUUUCCAAUUGCCUCAUUUUUGUUUUUUAGUUUAUUUGACUCAGGAUCCAAGUAACAUCUACACGUUGCCUUUUGUUUGUUUGUUUGUUUGACACAGAGUCUUGCUCUGUCGCCCAGGCUGGAAUGCAGUGGCGUAAUCUCGGCUCACUGUAACCUCCGCCUUCCGGGUUCAAGCAAUUCUCCUGCCUUAGCCUCCUGAGUAGCUGGGAUUACAGGUGCGCACCACCCCACCACGCCCAGCUAAUUUUUGUAUUUUUGGUAGGGACAGGGUUUCACCAUGUUGGUCAGAUUGGUCUCGAACUCCUGAUAUUGUGAUCCGCCUGCCUCUGCCUCCCAAAGUGCUGGGAUUACAGGCGCGAGCCCCUGCGCUGGCCCACAUGUUGCUUUUGAUUGCUGUACCUCUUGAGUCUCAGGCUCCCCUCGCUCUUACUGCAUUGGCUUCAUGCUCAGUCUCCACGUCUAUAAUGUGGGUAUAAUACUGCCAUUCCAGCCCCACACCUCUAAUGUGGAUAACAUACUACCAAUUCAGCCCCACACACCUUAGAAUAAGUCUCACUACAUCUCCUUGGUUCAAAAGUAGUCUCUGAACCAGUCACUGCAGCCAGGGAACCCAAGGCUUUAAUUAGCCAGGGCUGGUCACUUUCCAUUCCUGGAGUCAGAGUAGAGUUACUCCAGAUCUGGAUCAUAAUCCCAAAAGACACAGUCCAGAACACCAUAAUCCCGAAUGUUGAAAUUCCCAAAGAUGAAAAUCCCUAAAGUAUAAAUCUCUAAAGUCUAAAAUCCUGAACAUCUAAAAUCCCCAAAAUCACAAUCACAGAAUAGCUGCAUCAUGUUAGGCCAGCUCUUCGGACUAUCUCCAUGCAAUUGCCCAUAAUCUAUCCCCAUAAUACUCUUUUCAUAUGUUGAAUUUUCUUUUUAGUUCUUUUUCUUAUUUUAGUUUUUUUUCCACUAUUUUAAAGUUUCAGCAUGAUUUUUUAUAAUUCACUAUGCCAUCUAUUUCAUCUUUUCAUCAUUUCCAAUACUGGACAUAUACAUUGUGAAGAGACUUUUGGAAAAUUCUAAUUCAUUAAAUGCCUUUUUUGCAAAUUUAACUCCAUAAAAAUGCAUCAGCACAGCAUUGACUUUGUGUGUAAGCAUUGCGCAUAUACAUAAAAAUGUUGAAACAUCCUCAAUAAAUGAAGAGAUGGCCUUUUAUACAAAUCUGCGUUUGUGAAGAAAAUUUCUUGAGAUCUCAGCUCUUUGGGCAACUGCCUAUGUGGUAACUGCAUGUCACAGUUUUUUAUUGAUCUCAUCAAAAGAUUCUUUGUCACAGUAUUUCAGAUGACCAAAUUUAUAAAGCUGGGCACAAACAAUACCAACUGUAGUGAUAUGCAUUUGUACACUUCUCUUCUUGCCCUAUUUCUUUAUGAAUACAGAUGUCUGCUUAUAACUUCUAUACCUGUGCUACUGUCGUUGGAAUACCUGAGUGUUUAUGCUUGCAAAAAUAUUUGUGUUAUUAUUGUCUAUUUUAUUGUGUAAAAUGGCCUAUGAAGUGUUCUGUCAUGUUUUUAUAUGUUUCUUAAAUAAAUCCUCCUUUAAAAUGUAAAUAAAUAUCUUUCAAAUAAUUCUCUAUUAUUUCUUCCAGAAUUAUAUUUUCAGGAUUUUGAUCUUUUGGGAUUUCAGUAUUCAGGAUUCUGGUGUUUGGAAUUGUGUCUCUCAGGAUUAUGAUCGGGUCCCUCCCCACUCUAUCUAAUGUUAGCAUGCUGUAGAGAAUUUGGGUUUUCCAACCUGCAAGUCUCCAAAUUAUUUGACUCUCACCCAUCUUGGUUGCAGAUCACAGCCAAAAAAAGGCCUCUCUUAACAAAGCCGUAUUUUUUCCCUCUGUGCCUCUAGUCAGUUUUGAGCCUACAUUUAUCUCUUUCCUGUGGAUCUUACUAAAAGACACAAGAAAUAGCCAACACACUGCACCAUUCUAAAUGCUUUUCCAGUGAAUCCAUUAAUGGUGUACCAUGAGUAGGCUCCUGUCUCAGACCGAGGAGUCAAUAGGUGGCAGCAUAACUAGCUAUUUUGUUGUCACUUAACAAGGACUGCCAAUUUUCCAGUCCAGGCCAGCCUGCGCUAGCCUUCCCCAACCUCAAAUCAGCCAGUUGCACAUUUUAGGCUUAGUCACAUUCAACACUCACUUCUAGUACCAAUUCCUUUAUCACUUAAGAGUCUUUGCAUUGCUAAUGAUAGAAAACGUGACCAUACCAGCUUAAAUAAAAUAGAGAAUUUAUUUGCAUAAAUUAAAGGUCUAGAAAAAGGCCAUCUUCAGUUAUAGAUAGAUUCAGGGCUCAACCAACAACACCAGCACUUGGUUUUUCUCCCUCUUCCAAUUCCCAUUUUGUUGGUCUUGGUUUUAGACCCCAUGUGGUCAAAGGAUGAGUGCAGCAGGCCCAUCCCCUACAUCCUCAACAGAUCUGGUUCCAGCCUCAUCCCUCAGGGAUAGAGCUCGCCUCAGCCUACAAAUUUCCUUGAUUCUGAUGAUCACAAGCCAUCACCAGAAGUCUCUAGGGCCAAAUGAAUGCAAGGCUCUGAUUAGCCAGCCUUGAAUCACAUGCUUUUCCUCUGUCUGGAAUGGGAGUGAAUGCCUCUGGAUGCACAUGGUUUGAGAGUGAGCACGGGAUGAUUCUCCAUACAAACAAAUGGACGUGAUUAUAAGUAGGGGGAAUGGUUGCUGAGCUGCCAAAACACAACAGAAUACACUGCAGACUUUUCCCCAAGUAAGAUUACAUCAAUUUAUAUUAACAGGGUGCAGAAUACUACAAGGUUUGUUUUUAAUUUAUCUAUGUUUCUGAGAUUAUUUUUAAAUGAUCAACCCUGUAUGUAGCUGUACUGAUAAUUAUGUGGUGGAGAGGAUUAUUCCUUUGUUUCUGCUCUUUUAAAUCAAAUAAUUCCCAUAUUUUAACAUUUUGAAAAUAGAUUCUUACAACUAAUGCAUAUCUUUAAUCUGGUAGUGUUUCUUUUUCACCCUAAAAAUCUAUAAGGAGUCAUUCUGCAGUAUAAGAAGGAAUAAUGUAAGUUUUAGAACUGCGGGAUGCAGUAUUAUAAAACACCUUUCCACUACUGGGGAAAUACUGCACCAUAACAGGUAGUCAUGGAAACACAACUUGAAAAACCAGAAUUAUUUAAAACUUAUGUUGCCAUAUUUUACACAUGCCACUGUUGCACUGAUUCAGUCCAUGUUGACUGGGGGCCACGGCAGGAGGCUGUGAUUCUUCAGCACUUUUUCUACACUGGCUAGACCUACAUUAUUGUUUUAUAAUCUUCUGCCUGCUCUUGGUUUUUUAUUUCUAUAGAUUAAUAUGGAGGAUUCUUUAUGUGAUUGGUCUGCGAGCCUAUUGGUUAUUGUUUUACUCUGUCAUUAAGCUCAGACUGAUGCAUAUUAAAUGGGAAAGAGAUACGCAUUUAAAAUUCUCUUUAAGUCCAGAAUUGUGAUUGUCUUUAUUCAUCCAGGCUUUCAAUCCACUUAUCUCAGGCCUUUGGUUAUAGUAUAACAACCUCUCCCAUCCGCAUCACAGCCUUUCUCUCCACCCUCUUUCUUCUGCCUCUUCUUGUACUUACAGAAAGGAGGUAGGUGGUAUCACCCGAACCUGAAAUGAGGCUAAAGACAUUAAUGGCGCUGGACAGUGGAGUGGAGCCCAGGCUUUGGCCACUGCUCUGCUGCUGCCAGCUGUGUGACAUGAGCAGGAUGCCUAACUUCUCUGGACCCCUGUUUCUUCCUCUGUAAGUGGUGAUGUAGACUUUGAUCUCUGCAAGUCUCCUGCAGCCUUAAAGUUCUUUUCUUUUUAAAGAACGUGGCUGCUGGAAAAGCUGACACUGAGCUGAGAACUCCGCUUCACUGCGGAAGGCCAGACAGCACUGUUACAUCCAGCACCUGUGGGUCAUCCACUGCAGAGGUGGCUUCCAAAGCCUCUGAGGUCAGCAGUGUGGUUGUAGCUCUCCUCUACCCACCACAUGAUCUCUCCCCAUCUCCAGCUUUUCUUGCCUUAUUUUCUUUAUCUUUUUAUUUCCCCCCCUUCCUUUCUGAUUGUUCUAUUUGUUUUCAAUUUUCUUAAUCCAUUUUUCUCUUCACAUUGCCCAAUGGUGUAAGCCACCUGCACUGCAUAAGACUCUGCCUGCACUGCCAGGCCCACUGAUGGGCCAAGGGUUUUACCUGCUGACCUUUUCUCUGGAAAAUUUCCCUUUAACAGCUUCUCCCAAGAAGGCUUAAGUCUAGUCUUGGCAUUUGUUAUUUACCAUUUCAGGGGGAACAGUCUUAAGCUUUUAAAGGAACAUUAUGCUGGGCAGCGUGGUGGUUCACACCUAUAAUCCCAGCACUUUGGGAGGCUGAGGUGGACAGAUCACUUGAGGCCAGGAGUUGGAGACCAGCCUGGCCAACAUGGCGAAACCCCGUCUCUACUAAAAAUACAAAAAAAAAAUUAGCCAGGCGUGGUGGUGCACGACUGUAGUCCCAGCUAGGGAGGCCAAGACAUGAGAAUCGCUUGAACCUGGGAAGUGAAGAUUGCAAUGAACCAAGGUCAUGCCACUGCACUCCAGCCUGGGUGACAGAGUACGACUCUGUCUCAAAAAAAAAAAAAAAAAAAAAAAAAAAAAAGGAACAUUAUGCUGUAGUAGAAUUCGUAAGAAACAUUGAUUUUCUUUUCCAUUCAACAAACACUAUUUUCAAACACCUGCAUUAGAUGCUGAAGCAACAGCAGUCAAACACCUGCAUUAGAUGCUGAAGCAACAGCAGAAACAAGAUGGACAAGGUCCCUGCUCUCAUAGAGCUUGAAUUCUAGUGGAGAGAAACAUACAAGUAAAUAAACAGAUAAAUAAGACAGUGUCAAGCGGUGACGCAUGCUAUGCAUAAAAGAAAACAGCAGAAAUGGGUCAUGAGGGAGAGCAUUUUUGCUGACAUUUGAAGAAUAAAAAGGAACAAAAAGAUGAGUGUACCAGGCGUGAGUACCAGGCUUGCAAGUAAAAGGCCUGAAGAUGCAAAUGAGCUUGGUGCAUUUAAGGAACAGAAAGAUUUGGAAGGUAAAUUAGCAAGGCAGAAUAUUACUUGAGAUGAAGGCAGAGAGUUAAGGAGGGGCCAGAUCUCGUGGGUCCCUGUGGACCUAAGAGUUUGGACUUUUUAAGUGAAAUGAGAAGUCAUUGGAGGGUUUUAAGCAGGGGAGGAACAUUAUCUAAUUUAUGUCCUAACAUGCAUAGUAGACACCUGAUAAAUGUGUCCAAAGUUGACUGUAGGAAUAGACUCAAACUACACAACUACUCCCUUGCAUGUCUUGGGGACUGCAGCCUUCUAGGUGACAUACUCCCUUCUAAGUGAGCUUUUCCUAAGGUAGGGGUCUCCAACCAGUCUAUGGCCCCUUAGGAACCAGGCCACACAGCAGGAAGUGAGCAGCUGGUGAGCAAGUGUUCCCUCCUGAGCUCUGCCUCCUAUCAGAUCAGCUGCGCAUUAGAUUCUCAGAGGAGCAAGAAUCCUAAAGUGAACUGUGCAUGCGAGCUCCUUAUGAGAAUCUAAUGCCUGAUGAUCUGAGUUGGAGCAGUUUCAUCCUGAAACCAUCCCCACCCCCUGCCCCCACUCCGUGGAAAAAUUAUCUUCCACAAAACCAGUCCCUGGUGCCAAAAAGGUUAGGGACCACUCCCCUAAGGGAUGGAAAUAGCCAUGAAUGGUAUGUGUACUGAGAGAGAGAGAGAGAGAGAGAGAUAGCUAGAGAGAGAGAGAGAGAGAGUGUGUGUGUGUGUGUUUGGGGUGUCUUACUUAGAGAACUUCAAAAUAAUUCUGAAAAUACGUAGAGAAAUUGUCAUAUCGCCCAUGUUCUCUUUUUAGACCCAACUAUAAUUAGACUUCCCCAAAGAUUCACUCAGGCAUUUACUUAAUAGUUGAUCAAGUUUUCUGUUUUCCUGAGGGUUUGUAUCGCGGGAAGUGGCUGAUAGCUGUAGGCCUCCACCUCUGUCCAGCCCCAUGCCUGCAGGUAUUUAUUUGUGACCUAAGUCACGGGUGGACACCAGGCCAGAGUUAGACAAGAGGCGGUCCCUGCCUUCAAGGGGCUCCAGGCAAAGCAGAGGACUCUCAGUCACUUAUUCUUGGGUACUCCACUCCAGGAACUGUGCCCAUGGCCUGGCAUCAUGAAUCUGCUCAUGCAAUUAGACUCCUAUCUCAGGGAAUUUUGAGUUUAAAAGAUCCUUAGACAUCAUCUGUCCCAGUACUCCCCAGUAGGAGCACUUCUGGUAUUUUGGGUGGGACUGUCAUAAGCACCAUAGGAAAUUUCCCAUUCCUGGCCCCACCCACUGAAUGCUACAGGCCCCUGCCCCCACCAUUCCCACUCACUGCUCACCACCCCCAACAGCUACCUGAGUUGAAAAUUACUCAUCUAGCCCAGUUCCAUCACUUUACAGGUAAGGCAAUGUUAGACAACAUACGUUCUUUUCAUGCCUCUGGCCUCUGAUCCUAGCAGAAUCAGGACCCAACAUUCAGAUUUUACAAUGAAGCUAGUUUCUGAAAUAUGCCUCUCUUUUAAAUUCUUUGACUGUUACUGUUUUCUCAGAGUUAUAUACUAUGUGUUGCAUAUGUAAGUCUGAACCUUUAAGAUGGGUUAAGAAAAAAUUAUGAGCAUUUUCAGAUCGUUCUAUACAUAACUCAAGGUUUUGAUAAAAUGUUUUCUACAUGUAUUCCAUUGCCAUCCACCUCUUGAGUUCUUUAAUAAUGAGAAAUCUGACUUUCUUCCUUCCACCCUCUUUAUCUCUAUGCUUUUGUCAAGCAUCUUCUAGGAGAGUUACUGUUAUCCCAUUAAGUGUGGGGGACAGAAACAUUUGGCAUAGAAAGCUAUGGAUCUGCAGCUGACUUAAGCUGUAUAUUAUUACCCUGACUUGGGCACCAAAAUCACGUUUCAAAACUCAUUUGCUGCCAAGUAUGGUAGCUCAAGCCUGUAAUCCCAGCAAUCUGGGAAGCUAAGAUGGAAGGAUCACUUUGAAGCUAGGAGUGCAAGACCAGGCUGGGCAACAAAGCAAGAUCCCAUCUCUACCAAAUAUAAAAAUAAAAUAAAUUAGCCAGGUGCAGUGGCAUAUGCCUGUAGUCUCAGCUACUCAGGAGGCUGAGGCUGGAGGAUUGCUCGAACCCAGGAGGUCAGGGCCACAGGGAGCUAUGAUUACGCCACUGCACUCCAGCCUAAGUGACAGCAAGACUGUCUCUCUAAAAAAAAAGAAAUAAAUAAAACAAAACCAAAAAAAGAACCUCAUUUGCCUUCAUACACCUGACCUGCUCUCUUUACCUGCAUUUGUAACUUUCUCCCCACACACUUGAAUGCCCUGUAAAUGAGAAGAAGCCCUUAGCCUAAUGAAGCGAUAAGAUUUAUCAGCAAGACUGUUGAACGCAUAACUGCCCAAGAUGCCUGUCCCUCCCCCUCCAGCACCCCCGCCGCCCCCGACGUUUGCACUGGCCAAUACAGAGAAGCCUACCUUGAAUAAGACAGAGCAGGCUGGGAGAAAUGCUCUCCUUUCUGAUAUCAGCAAAGGGAAGAAACUAAAGAAGACGGUCACCAAUGACAGAAGUGCACCAAUACUGGACAAACCUAAAGGAGCUGGUGCUGGAGGCGGUGGUGGUGGCUUUGGUGGAGGCGGCGGAUUUGGCGGAGGAGGUGGUGGCGGAGGCGGUGGAAGUUUUGGAGGGGGCGGACCUCCAGGUCUGGGAGGAUUGUUCCAGGCUGGAAUGCCGAAGCUGAGAUCCACGGCCAACAGGGAUAAUGAUUCUGGAGGAAGCCGACCACCAUUGUUGCCACCGGGAGGAAGAUCCACAUCUGCGAAACCCUUUUCACCCCCAAGUGGCCCAGGGAGGUUUCCUGUGCCUUCUCCAGGCCACAGAAGUGGUCCCCCAGAGCCUCAGAGGAACCGAAUGCCGCCCCCAAGGCCCGACGUGGGCUCAAAGCCUGAUAGCAUUCCUCCUCCAGUACCUAGUACUCCAAGACCCAUUCAAUCAAGUCCGCACAACCGGGGGUCCCCACCAGUGCCCGGAGGCCCCAGGCAGCCCAGCCCCGGGCCCACUCCUCCCCCUUUCCCUGGAAACCGCGGCACUGCUUUGGGAGGAGGCUCAAUACGUCAGUCCCCCUUGAGCUCCUCCUCGCCCUUCUCCAACCGGCCUCCCCUGCCGCCUACCCCCAGCAGGGCCUUGGAUGACAAACCCCCUCCACCACCUCCUCCAGUGGGCAACAGGCCCUCCAUCCACAGGGAAGCGGUUCCCCCUCCUCCUCCUCAGAACAACAAGCCUCCAGUGCCUUCCACUCCGCGGCCUUCGGCCUCCUCACAGGCCCCACCUCCGCCGCCACCUCCCAGCAGGCCCGGGCCGCCUCCUCUGCCUCCAAGUUCCAGCGGCAAUGACGAAACCCCAAGACUCCCACAGCGGAAUCUGUCCCUCAGUUCGUCCACGCCCCCGUUACCUUCGCCAGGACGUUCAGGUCCUCUUCCUCCCCCGCCCAGUGAGAGACCCCCACCUCCAGUGAGGGACCCGCCAGGCCGAUCAGGCCCCCUCCCACCACCUCCUCCAGUAAGCAGAAACGGCAGCACAUCUCGGGCCCUGCCUGCUACCCCUCAGUUGCCAUCCAGGAGUGGAGUAGACAGUCCCAGGAGUGGACCCAGGCCUCCCCUUCCUCCUGAUAGGCCCAGUGCUGGGGCACCUCCCCCACCUCCACCAUCAACAUCUAUUAGAAAUGGCUUCCAAGACUCUCCAUGUGAAGAUGAGUGGGAAAGCAGAUUCUACUUCCAUCCGAUUUCCGAUUUGCCACCUCCAGAGCCAUAUGUACAAACGACCAAAAGUUAUCCCAGCAAACUGGCAAGAAACGAAAGCCGGAGUGGAUCCAACCGAAGAGAAAGGGGUGCUCCACCACUCCCUCCCAUCCCGAGGUGAUCUUUGCCUGCUCUUCUCUACCCAAGCUCAAGAGCUGCUUCUGUUGCUAUCUAAGAACUGCAUACCCUCCUCCCUGCUUCUUCCCUUGUGCCUCAUGUAUGGGCAGGAGGAAAGGUGGGAGGGGGAGUGGGAAUAUGCGUGUGUGGGUGGGAAUCGGUAAGAAAUGCACCUAGCUUUUCAUAUUGUGUUUAUUCUCCAGGCUAUUGCUUGCUUCAGCUGCAGCCUGCCUGUGCUGGCUGCUGGGGUCGAUAGGCUUUUGUCGUAAUAGGCAGAGAUGACUUGCAUCCCAGCUUUCCACCAACCAAAUUCAAACAUUCACUGCUUAUUUGUUACAGACUGUAAUUAUUAAAGUCCCUGAGAGCUGUUUUCUCCCGUUCCUUUUUCGCAUGCUUGGCCUCCUCUCUGUUUCUAUGAACCACAGACCACCUAAGCAAGCUGCUGAGUAAGGGCUCACUGGAAACUUGCAGUCACAGGAUGUCCAAUCUUUGGCAGUCCGAGCUUGGCUCUAGGACAGAGCUGUCCAAUAGAAAUAUAAUGUGAGCCCCAUAUACAAUUUUUACAUUUCUAAUAUAUUUUAAACAAGUGAAGUUAAUAUGCAUCCAAAAUAUUUCAACCUGUAAUCAACAUAAAAUUUUAAUGAGAUAUUUUAUAUUAUUUUUUGGUACUGAAUCUUCAAAAUCCAGAGUGUAUUUUACACUUACCGCACAUCUCCAUUCAGACUAGUCACAUUUUUAAGUGCUCAGUAGCCACAUGUGGCUGGUGGCUACUGGAUUAGACAGCACGAGUCUGGAAGAUGGAAGCUAGUGCAGAAACCUCUUGUUUAAAAAACAAAAAAGGCAAGAUGGGCUUGAGCGAUUCAAGAGGCAACUAAAAAUAAAAUUAGGACCCAGCACCUUGUUUGACACACAGUUUGACCUUCGAUUUUCCUCCCUUAACUUCCCUCUUCCCUUAAUAUCUGUAUACAAGUGUUGCUUCAAAGUACCAAGGUCAGAAAUUGAUUGAGUACGGUUUACUAAAGUCAUGUGGAAUAAAGCCAUUGGAAACAAAUGGAAAGCCUGUCGGGACUUCUGGGCUCAGAACCAGCUGGCUCACGCACUCCACUUGUCAGCUGGACUUCUGCCUUGUGAAAUGGAAGCAGCCUUUGUUCCUUUCUGGCUGAGCAAGCUCCUGAGGCUGGGAGAGACUAGGAAGGCUUGGUAGGAGGGGAAAAAAGUCAGGAAAAUAUAUCAAAUCAGAAACAUGGAAGAAGAAGGGAACCGAUUUGAGUUGGUGGGCAAAACUCUAAAAAUCUAAAUCUGAUGCUUAUGUAAGGGUUGAGCGAAUUAGGGAGAUUGCUAGUGGAAAUUGGAGGGAAUUUGUUUUGCAUCAUUUGUCUAGGAUCUAUGCAAAUAUAGCUCCACUAAAGGACCAUAGGGAAGAGCCAGCCUUGCCUUUUCUUAUAUGAUUUUGUUUACAAAAUUUUACUGGGACUUUUAAAUCUAGCUAUAGAGUUGGGAAAAAAUAUUUCCACUUAGAUAUUUUACAUGGUUUUGUUUAAAAUUACCAUUACUUGUUUUUUAAAAACACAUGACCACAUAUGUAUAUGUAUAUCUACCUAAACAUUGUAUCAUGGUUUCAGUAUGUUAUUCAUGUAUUACUGGGAGAUGCUACCAAGAAACCAACCCAAAGAAAAUUCUGAAAAAUACAUUUCUAUUUAUAGAAUAAAUGUUUCAUUUAUAUAAAAGCAAAAGAACUUAGAGUUCUAAUAAAUGGGAUGUCUAAUAAAUUAUGAAGUUACUGAUUUGAAUAUAUUAUAUUUCUAUAACUUCCUUGCCAAAGUCCUGAUUUAGUACAUUAGAGAACCUGUGUUUCCUCUCUCCUCUACCAUUCAUCUCUCUUCCAUACAGUCAUUUGGGCUUUUUACUCAAAGAGAAUCAAGAAAUAAUAAGGUAUAACAAGCUUGGCAAAGUGUUGGCUUUUUAAAAAAAAAUUUUUUUAAUCUCUAGCAGUUUGGUAAUUUAGCAGCAUCAUUUAUUUGGGAUUCUUUUAUCUGAUUUCAACAGUGAAAAACAUCCCUAUGAUAAAGCCUAAUGACCCAUUUCACAAAAGAUGGAAUUUGCCCUUCCUAGAAAAUAUGACGGAGAAAAGUCUGACUCAGAGAAAGUGGGUCUGAAUUUUAUAAGGGGUAGUAAGAAUUGGACAAUUCCUUUGCAUAUCUGAACUUGGCAGGUACCGUUCUAAAUCUGAAACAGGGUGAUAGCUCAAAGUUGCCAUUCAUCCAGAAUAGAUUGUUUUAGAAUGUAGUGUUUAAGUGACUGUUUCAUUAAUACACCUACACCCUUUCUUUGAAAGUUUGCAACCUAAUUGCAUCUAAAACUAUGAAUAAGUUCUGUGGUAAAAUCUUAAACUAUGGAAAAUUACAAAAAUGAAUUUUUCUUCCCUGAAAUCAGAGCUUACAUGUGUGUUUUUUUAUAACAUUUUCAGAUAAAUGUAUUCAACAUGUAAUACAGUAUUUUAACAUUCACCUCUUAUUUUAUAUUGAAAUGUAUUACAGUAUUAAAACUCAGUGUUCAGUAUUUAUUUCACUAUGCAUUUUAUUUAGUAAAAGCCAGGAGAAAUGUUUAAUCCAAUGGUGCCUUACUUUGUGAUUUAAAAGAAAUCAACUUUUUUUUAUGUCUAAGUAGUAGAUUAUUUGCAUAUUUGUAAAAACUGUUAGGUCUUUAUAUUUUAAAGUGUAAUACCAGUUUUGUUAUUUUAGUAGCAGAAAUGGGAUGAUUGUUAAAGUUCCCCAAAAAUGUUGGCAUGAAAUUAAUUUUUCCCUCCUUAUAGUCAAGGACCGUAGAGGAAGAAAAACUUUUUUUUCAUACCAUGCACUAUGUAAACAGACACAUUUUGCUAUCUGUGUCAUCAGGAUAGUGUAAGUGGUAGGGUAGAGACUACCCUAGACAUCUGCAUCUUUGUAAGUUAGCCAGACAAUAAAGAAAAGCAGAAUGA